GAGUGCGCAGGCGCUGAGUCCCUGCUCGGCUGUCUCGGUGGUCGCCGCCGGGGUCUGAGCCCGGGAAGACCGAGGUAAGGGGGCUGGCGAGAGUGUGGGUGUGUCUGAGGGCGUGGGCGGCGCGCCCGCCACUGCGUGGACGUUCCUGCCAAGGCGCGCGUGGGUUUGCGCAUCCACGAUGGCGUGGGCGUCUGCGCGGGUGCUUGCGUGGGCGGUGGGCUCGCGCCUGCGUGGGUUCUCGGCCCGCCACGGCGUGGGGUUUGCGCCCUUCGCUGCUGUGGUUCUCGGGGCUUGUGCGCCCAAGUGUGAAGUUGGCGCCGCGUGUGAGGCGAGCCGUGUGUGCCUGUGUGUGAGGGAGCUAUGUCGGGACCGCGGAUGUGUAUCGCUGCGUGACCCACGCGAAGGAAACAAUGGAGCCAUUGGGAAGCCGGGAGUGGGUGUGUGACGCUGACUGUGAAGAUUUGUGUUUCUGGAGUGUGUGCGUGUGUCAGUGUCAGGCUGAUGUGGGCGUUUAUUGUAGCCUUGGGUUACUGUGUGACUUGCCUGGGCGUCUGUCUGCCACUUAGCGUCAGUGGCUUUGCGGUUAUGAGUGUGUGACUGUGCCUUUCUGGUGUAUAUCUCACUGUAACCAUGGAAAUGGAGGCCCACAGGGGAAGAAUUCUUAGCAGCUCUAAGAUGUGAUGGGCUGCCCUGGAAAUCUGUGGAACUGUUUAAUUGUGCAUGACUUUCCUCCUUGGUAAAAUAGCAUAUUAAUAGCACCUGCCUGGGUGUUAUUGGGAAGAUUAAAUGGGAUGACGUAGCUGAAACACCCUGCACAGAGCUUGUCACAUACUAAUCACCGUGUUUAGGUGUUGGUUAUGGUGCUGGUGGUCGUUUUUCUUUGACCCUAUACAGAGGCAGAGGUAGUGGUGAAUACUGGAGGACUUUGCAUCUCUGAGCUUCGGACUGGGCUAUCUUUGUCCACAUACCAGGGCAUCUGACCAUCUCCAGUUGAGCAGUGGUGCGCUGCCCCCGCCAACCACCUGCGUCGUCAGUUUUCUGCAUGUGUACAUUUGAGUGGAGGACAGAGCCCUCCACUGACGCUAAGUAUGGUUGUGUCCCCUUCCUACCAAGGUAGCUUGGAAAAAUAAGAGCAUGGACUGUGGCGCCCCGCUGUCUGGUGUUGACUCCUGGUUUCACCACUGGCUGGCUGUGUGACUGAGAGAGCUUACUUAAGUCCACCACUCCUCGGUUCACUUGUAAAACAGUAGUAAUAACAGAACCAACCUCAGGUUUAUGGUGAGCAUAAGUAGAACUUGGCACAAGGAAGUGCCACAUCAAUGAUCAUCGUUUUAUUAUUAGCAUAAUAACCGCAGGCGUCCCACACCUGGAGAAUAAAAUCCAUAGGUAGAAAUGCAAAAGGAUGAGCCCCAGAGUAAGGGUUGCAGGUCCAGAGGUAAAAUAACUUGGACGUCUAGAUCAGGGCUUAGGUUCAGAAUUGUGUAGGCAGGGUCCUGGGAGGGCAGCAUUAGGGUAGAGGAGGUGGGGUCAGGAACAAAGGAUCUUCCUGAUGGAGAUGUCCCUAGGGAGCCCAUGGGGUCAAGAACAGAACUUUGAAGUGUCAGGGACUAAGGGAUGUUUCCAUAUAACACAUGGGUCUGGAAAUGUUUCUGUCCAGACCAGUGUUUCACAGCCUUGGCACUGUGACAUUUGGGGCCAGAUAGUUUUUUGUUGGGAGGUGGGAGGGGCUGCUAUUCUAUGUAUUAUAGGAUGUUGUGCAGCAACCCUGGGCUCUAUUUACCAGGCCAGUAGCACACCGCGCCUCCCUCUGGGUUGUGACAAGCGAAAAAAAAAUGUCUCCAGACACUGUCAGAUGUCCCCUGCAGGGGCAAAAUCACUCUGAUUGAGAGGACCGUGAUGCAAGCGCAUGGACAGACCGAAGGCAUGAUGACAGGGAGAAGAGUAAGGGAGCUGGGGAAGGCGGGGCACGGAGAGAUGAUAAAAGGAUAGUGUUCUGAGAUGAGAAGAAACGGCCUGCAGCCCGGGUAAGCUCCGAGAUGCAUUCAUUCAUUCAGCCAGUGAGUGCCUACCAUGGAUUGGGCACUGUGCUAGUCUCUCAACAAAACAGGCAAGGUUUUUACUCAGCUGGAACUUGCAUUUAGUAGGAGAGACAAAAAUAAAGUCUAUAAUAGGUGCUGAUAGGUACUUUGAAAAGUAAAGCAGGGUAAAGGGAUUACAGGGUGUUUGGCAGGUGUUCUUUUUGGAGUCAACAUCCAGGUCUCCCAUGGGCAUUUUGGUCAACUCCAGAGCCAGGAAGGACCACCAGCAGUGACCCUUUGGUAUCACUUGAUUGGGGAAUCUAAGAGUUUGACUUUGAUCUUAACCAAAGACUUUUCUCUUCACUGAGGUCUGGACUUCAACAGAAAGAGGUCAGAUCUCUAGCCCUGUCCUUGAGACUCUGAGACUCGAACGUUAUUCUAAACGAUGCCUUCAAUGUUACUCUCACCUUGGAAUGCUUUAUUUAAAAAAAGAAAAAAAAGGGCGGGUCAGACUCAAUCCCCAGAGAUUCUGAUUUAAUUGGUCUGGCAUAGUGAACUGCCAUCAGCUGUGACUAUUUAUUAGAAAGCUCCCAAGAGACUAAUGUACGCACAGGGUUAAGAGCUACAGCUCUGAGUGCCUGCAGCUCAGGCUCCUUUGGGGCCUCUGGGAAUGAGAUAAAUUGAUUUGGAGGAGUCAGGGGGAGGAUGCAAGUGACCUCUGCUUGGCUAUCUUAUCAAAAACAGUCCUCACAGCUGCACUUCCCUGCAGUAGGGGUAUUCCUAGCCCCAUCCUGCAAGUGAGGUAACCUAAUGUGUUCCCGGGCAAAGUGGGGAAAUGGCAGGCUAGACAUGCAUAUGCAUAGCCUGUGUUCUUCCUGUGACAGCUGUGCUGACGUCUUUGGAGAAAUUGCCUACGUAUGUCCCUGGCCUCUGGGGCUGGCAGGUUCAGGCCAGGAGUGAUUUUUGAAUAUUUGACAGCUGGUACAGCAAAAGCUGACUGGCCCAAAGGAGGCAAUGAGGCUGUGGCAGUGCAUUUAAUGGCUGGUUUUCAGUAUAUCAGGACCCUCCCCCAAUUCAAUACCCAGCACAGCCCCCAAGGCUCAAAGGGGUGCCAGGGCAGGAGGGGAAGGCCCCUCAGUUAUUUGCCUCAGAAGGGAGGCACAACCACGGUUCAGUAACUCUUUGAAGCAUGUUCCCAUCCAGGUUCCAGCCGUCCUCACCUCAGGAGGACAUAGCUUUGUGCCUUUCAAAGCCCUUUCUCAUCUAUCAUCAGGGACUCGGAAGACGAGCCAGGUUUACAGCCCUGCCUUGAUGUGUAGAGUGGUUUUCAUCGUCAUGGCCUUCAAGUUGAGUAGGCUGAGGAGGAAGAGGAGGAGCUGGUCUUACUGUCUCAGAGGUGGAAGAGGUGGAGGAGCCGGAAGGGGGAGGCCGGAGAGGUAGGCACACUCAGUGUAACUUCUAUUGAAAAAAAUCUGCAUAUAAGUGGACCCUCACAAUUCAAACUAACAUGGCUCAAGGGUCAACUGUAUUGUGAGUUGAAAAGGAAAAGGAAGGCAAGCAAUGACCAUGUUCCAGUUACCGAAGACAUCACAUGUAAAUAUCCUAACAGCAGAGGUGAGGUAGGUUUUCUUUACCCCAUUGUAUAGAUGAGCAAACAGGCUUUGUGUAACUUUUUCACAGCCAGUAAUUGGCAGAGGCAAGCUUUGAAUCCAGGAUUACCUAAUAUCAAACUGCUGUUCUUUCUUCCCCAGUAGUGCCGAGUUCCUUGAAGAAAAUUAUUUUAUGGACAAUGUAUGAGUCUGUUUUCGUGCUGCUGAUAAAGACAUACCCAGACUCACAGUUCUACGUGGCUGGGGAGGCCUCACAAUCGUGAUGGAAGGUGAAAGACACGUCUUACAUGGCCACAGGGAGAAUGAGAGUCCCUGUACAGAACCAUCAGAUCACAUGAGACUUACUCACUGCCAUGAGAACAGCAUGGGGGAAACCGCCCCCAUGAUUCAGUUAUCUCCCACCGGGUCCCUCCCACAACACGUGGAAAUUAUGGGAGCUAUAAUUCAAGAUGAGAUUUGAGUGGGGACACAGCCAGACCAUAUCAGACAAGAAUCAUCUUCUCAAAUUUGGGGUGCGUGGCUGAGUGCACACACCUGUGAAAACUGCGGGAUGAAUGCAUUACAACUUCCUGGAACAAGUCAUUUUACCUAAGUAAUUGGAAGGGGAAAGCCAACUGAUCUGCUUAUCUGUCAUGCCACCAACAUCUUCCCCGGAUUUCUGCAAAGCUACCUACCCUGCCUUACCAGCUCUCUGCCCAUCUCUCAGUGUGGACCCUAAAGGGGGAGGAAAGGAUGCCUUCUGCACGGGGGAAAUCCAAAUCCAAGGCACCUAUAACAUUUGGGGACUUAGCCAUCUACUUCUCCCAGGAGGAGUGGGAAUGGCUGAGCCCCAUUCAGAAGGAUUUGUAUGAAGAUGUCAUGUUGGAGAAUUACCGGAACCUGGUCUCGCUUGGUCUUUCCUUUCGGAGACCAAAUGUGAUCACCUUAUUGGAGAAAGGGAAAGCACCCUGGAUGGUAGAGCCAGUAAGAAGACGCCGGGCUCCUGACUCGGGGUCUAAAUGUGAGACCAAGAAGUUACCUCCAAAUCAAUGCAACAAAUCUGGGCAAAGCAUCUGCCAGAAACUAGUUUCUGCACAACAAAAAGCUCCUACACGAAAGAGUGGCUGCAACAAAAAUUCAGUCCUAGUAAAACCUAAGAAAGGGCAUUCAGGGAAGAAACCUUUAAAAUGUAAUGACUGUGGUAAAACCUUUAGUCGAAGCUUCUCUCUUAAACUUCAUCAGAACAUUCAUACAGGAGAGAAGCCUUUUGAAUGCAGUAAUUGUAGAAAAGCUUUCAGACAGAUCUCAUCCAUCCUACUUCAUCAGAGAAUUCACAGUGGAAAGAAAAGCCAUGAAUGCAAUAAAUGUGGGGAAAGCUUCAAUCAAAGAACAACCCUUAUUCUACAUAUGAGAAUUCAUGAUGGAAAGGAAAUUCUUGACUGUGGGAAGGCCUUGAGUCAAUGUCAGUCUUUCAAUAUACAUCAGAAAAUUCAUGUUGUUGGGAAUGUCUGCCAGUGCAGAAAGUGCGGAAAAGCCUUCAAUCAGAUGUCAUCCCUUUUACUUCAUAAGAAAAUUCACAAUGGAAAGAAAACACAUAAAUAUAAUAAAUGUGGGAGAGGCUUCAAAAAGAAAUCAGUCUUUGUUGUACAUAAAAGAAUUCAUGCUGGAGAGAAAAUCCCUGAAAAUGCGAAGGCCUUAAGUCAGAGUCUACAGCAAAGAAGUCACCAUUUAGAGAAUCCUUUUAAAUGCAGAAAAUGUGGGAAAUUAUUUAAUAGGAUUUCACCCCUGAUGCUUCACCAGAGAAUUCACACUUCAGAGAAACCGUACAAAUGUGAUAAAUGUGACAAGUUCUUCAGGCGGCUUUCAACCCUUAUUCUGCAUCUAAGAAUUCAUAAUGGAGAAAAACUAUACAGAUGCAAUAAAUGUGAGAAGGUCUGCAAUCGGCAUUCAUCCCUUAUUCAACAUCAGAAAGUUCAUACAAAGAAAAAGAAACUAUUUGAGUGUAAGGAAUGUGGGAAGAUGUUUUCUGGAACUGCAAACCUUAAAAUACAUCAGAAUAUUCAUUCUGAAGAGAAACCUUUCAAAUGCAAUAAAUGUAGUAAAGUUUUCGGCCGCCAAUCAUUUCUUAUUGAACAUCAAAGAAUUCAUACUGGAGAAAAACCCUACCAGUGUGAGGAAUGUGGAAAAGCCUUCAGCCACCGAAUAUCUCUCACACGACAUAAGAGAAUUCAUACUGAAGAUAGACCCUAUGAAUGUGAUCAGUGUGGGAAGGCCUUCAGCCAGAGUGCACACCUCGCCCAACAUGAAAGAAUUCACACUGGAGAGAAGCCAUAUACAUGCAAAACAUGUGGUAAGGCCUUUAGUCAGCGCACAUCUCUUAUUCUACAUGAAAGAAGUCAUACUGGAGAGAAACCCUAUGAAUGUAAUGAAUGUGGGAAGGCAUUUAGCAGUGGCUCAGACCUUAUUCGACAUCAGAGAAGUCAUUCUUCAGAGAAACCCUAUGAAUGUAGUAAAUGUGGGAAGGCAUAUAGUCGGAGUUCAUCCCUGAUUCGACAUCAGAAUACACAUUCUGAAGAAAAAGCCUAAGGUUGUUUUAAAUCUAUAAAAUCAACGAAUGAGGCUAUCAAACAUAUGGCAAAUAUGUAUUUGUCUAUAAUGUAAAUUUUGUGUAUAUGGGACCAUUUGAUGAUAUGUCCCACUUUGAAAGCCAAAGAGCAAAAGUCAUUGGUGAUUUUGACCUCAGGAUUUGAAAUUAACUGAAGGAAACUCAGAAGUUUGGUCAGUCAUUGUGAAUGAAGAUCAUUUUUCAUUUGAUAAGAAUUACUGGCUGGGCGCAGUGGCUUACACCUGUAACCCCAGCACUUUGGGAGGCUGAGACAGGCGGAUCACGAGGUCAAGAGUUUGAGACCACGGUGAAACCCUGUCUCUACUAAAAAAUACAAAAUUAGCUGGGCGUGGUGGUGCGCACCUGUAAUCUCAGCUACUGGAGAGGCUGAGGCAGGAGAAUCGCUUGAACCCAGGAGGUGGGGGUUGCACCGAGCAGAGAUUGCACCACUGCACUCCAGUCUGGGCAACAGAGCAAGACUCUGUGUCAAAAAAAAAAAAAAUUACCGAUAUUUUACUUCCAGCAUAGUUUUAAAGAUAAUUUAUUGGUCACAUACAACAAAAUAGAAUUGUGAAGUCCAUUAUAGGGCUCUGAGCCUGAUUUAAGGUCACAGAAAAAAGAAUUUGAGUCUGUUUCUCAGAUCUAGAAUUAUCAAAUAUAAGGAACUUCUCGGCAAAACAGGGUGCCACUUUCAGCUGACAAACUUGUGGGUGAGAAUAAAGAAAAGUGAGUCUUUAGGUAGAUAAAGUUGUCACUCAUAAUGGUGUGUAACAGUAGAAACCUUACUUUACCAUCUCCACGGAUAUGAGGAUAUAUGAUCUUCAUGGUGUGAACGUCUAACUUGGCUGAGACAAGCUAUCAGUAAAAGAACCAAGAUAUAGUGAAGAAUGAGGAUUUCAGAGCCAGGAGAAAUCAGUAUUGUUUUAUUUGGAAAUAAAUCAUCUAUAUUUAUAUGAGUAAACAUUGGUAUUUUCAUGUAACAAUACUGGUAUGCAAUAAGUGGUGUAAUAUGAGUUGUUAUGGACUGAAUGUUUAUGUCCCUCCCAAAACUAAUUAUGUUAAAAUCCUCACCAUCAAUGUGAUGUUACUUGGAAAUGAGGCAUUUGGGAGGCAAUUAGGAUUAGAUGAGGUCAUGAGGGUGGAGCCCUCGUGAUGGGAUUAGUGCCUUUAUAAGAAGAGACAUCAGGCUGAGCCCGGUGGCUCAUGCCUGUAAUCCCAGCACUUUGGGAGGCCAAGGCGAGUGGAUCAUGAGGUCAGGAGAUUGAGACAAUCCUGGCUAACACGGUGAAACCCCGUCUCCACUGAAAAAAAAUACAAAAAAUUAGCCAGGCACAGUGGCAUGUGCCUGUAGUCCCAGCUACUCGGGAGGCUGAAGGAGAAGAAUCGCUUGAACCCAGGAGGCGGAGGUUGCAGUGAGCCAGGAUCACGCCACUGUACUCCACCCUGGGCGACAGAGCGAGACUACGUCUCAAAAAGACAUCAGAAAGCCUGCUUGCUCUCUGCACCAUGUGAGGAUGCAGGAAGAAGCCAGCUGUCUACAGAACAGGAAGAGAACCCUACGAGAACCUAACCAUGCUGGCGACCUGUUCUCAGACUUCCAGACUUCAGAACUGUGAGAAGUAAAUUGUUGUUUAAGCCACCCAGUCUAUGAUGUUUUGUUAUGGCAGCCCCAGCUAAUAUAUGGAGUGGAAAGCCUAGAUUUAUCUACUGGGUUCUUUUCCUGUCAGCAGUUCAACAUGUGUAGUAGCUUUCAGUCUCUGCUGUUUGUGCCAAAUAUAUAAGAAAUAAAAUCAGAUAACUUUUUUGUAAUUGGA